GCAGUCAGUCCGGUGUUUGCAAAUAUUGUGUGGGCUCCGCGCGCUGCGGGCUGCGGGAGGGUCCGGCCGGGCGUCUCUGCGAGCCUGGAGUUUGCAUGAAACUUUCACCUGCGCUCCGGGGAGACUUUCGGCUCCGGCUCCCACCGCGCGCCUCGCCGCCCUCGCGACCGCGGGCUCCGUCCAACCCGGCCCGACAUGGACGUGCUCCCCAUGUGCAGCAUCUUCCAGGAGCUCCAGAUCGUGCACGAGACCGGCUACUUCUCGGCGCUGCCGUCUCUGGAGGAGUACUGGCAACAGACCUGCCUAGAGCUGGAACGUUACCUCCAGAGCGAGCCCUGCUAUGUUUCAGCCUCAGAAAUCAAAUUUGACAGCCAGGAAGAUCUGUGGACCAAAAUCAUUCUGGCUCGGGAGAAAAAGGAGGAAUCCGAACUGAAGAUAUCUUCCAGUCCUCCAGAGGACACUCUCAUCAGCCCGAGCUUUUGUUACAACUUAGAGACCAACAGCCUGAACUCAGAUGUCAGCAGCGAAUCCUCUGACAGCUCCGAGGAACUUUCUCCCACGGCCAAGUUUACCUCCGACCCCAUUGGCGAAGUUUUGGUCAGCUCGGGAAAAUUGAGCUCCUCUGUCACCUCCACGCCUCCAUCUUCUCCGGAACUGAGCAGGGAACCUUCUCAACUGUGGGGUUGCGUGCCCGGGGAGCUGCCCUCGCCAGGGAAGGUGCGCAGCGGGACUUCGGGGAAGCCAGGUGACAAGGGAAAUGGCGAUGCCUCCCCCGACGGCAGGAGGAGGGUGCACCGGUGCCACUUUAACGGCUGCAGGAAAGUUUACACCAAAAGCUCCCACUUGAAAGCACACCAGCGGACGCACACAGGAGAAAAGCCUUACAGAUGCUCAUGGGAAGGGUGUGAGUGGCGUUUUGCAAGAAGUGAUGAGUUAACCAGGCACUUCCGAAAGCACACCGGGGCCAAGCCUUUUAAAUGCUCCCACUGUGACAGGUGUUUUUCCAGGUCUGACCACCUGGCCCUGCACAUGAAGAGGCACCUCUGAGGGAGCAGAGAGGUGGAUCCUGUAGGCUAAAAGGCUUCCAGGCUGAGAGCCGGCCGUGGAAGGAGGGAUGCGUGUUCCAGCCAAAGCAUGCCGUUCUGCACCCUACCCAGUUGCCUCCAGGGCCUCUCCUUGGAAGGUCUUUUGAGGGCUAAAAAGGUCCUGUAAGAAGCGGCAUAGCACCCGUGGUGCAUGGUAUGUGGGUGACCCUGGACUCGCCACUGGUACCCGCCCUUCCGAGCGGCGCCUAAGCCUUUGCCGUGAGCAUGCACACUGAGAAUGCUAAUGGUUGGGUUGAUUGUAUGUUGAGGAUCUAUUACUGACCGUAUGAUGAGGCCAACUUUUUUUCCUUGUGGUUAGCAAGACUGCAAGAGAUGGAAAAAAAGUAGUUUGAAUGUUUUGUGUGUAAGGAGUAUACCAUGAGAUGAGAUGACCACCAAUCAUUUCCUUGGGGGGAGGGGGUGUCUGCACCUUAGAAAAAAAAAGAAAAAUCAAAAAAACAAAAAAACAAAAACAAAAAAAGAAGGAAAAUCUUGGAGGGUGGGCGUGGGAACUCAGGACCCCAGAGUGGCGAGUGGUGUGGGGAGGGAGAGCCUCUCUCCCCCUUUUCUGUGUGAGAGGAACUCUUAGUGUCUGGUGCAGCUAUUAAAUGUGCAAUGUGUCAAGUAGCUUGUUUUACACGCUACAACAUAGCUCAUUUGUAACCCAUUGUAUAAGCUGUGUAUUUACAAAUAUAACACAACAAUUUAACUUUUCCUUAGAAUACAAAAAGUCAUGCAUGGUCUGGGGAACUAUAUGCUUUUCCAUUUUUAAGUCAGGACUGCAAUACUGAUUCCAGUUAAUGAGCAGCUAAGAUCCAAUCUGUCUAAUACAGUGACCCCCUAGCCAUCCGGGCCUGGCAAUAUACAAUUUUUUUUCCCCUCCAAGUUUGUAACACUCCCCUUCCAGAAAGGCAUUGUGCAACACAGGAUUAUUUUUAAAUGAUUCUGAAUUUGAAUUAACUUUUUGGAGAAUUCUGUGAUGCCCUUAGAAGAAAUUGGACACGUAUUGAGUGUCACAAAGCUGGGGCUGGGAAUUGCUGGUCUAAUGUUUCAUUAGACUUAAGAACCUAAAAUUUUUCUCAGUUGGGUGGAUAAAACCACUAACGCUUAGAAACUGUUUUCUCAUGCAGCUAUGUUUCUCUUAUUUAUGCCUUGAGGACUAAUUUCUGGUUUUCUAGCUGUUAAUGCACUGUUGACCUUCAUAAUGGUGCCUUACGCAAGCGAUCCCUUCUGUGGGGGUCUCAUACAGGGGUGUGGGCGAUGCAUGCUUUAUUAAGGCUCUUGUUUCACCUGGCAGUGUACUGUAUCAACGUAUAAUACAGAAAAAAAAUCUCUUUAAGGUCCUCCUUCACAAAGACAUAGAGUGAAACUCCCUUUACAUGUCAGUAUUUGUUCAACACUUUAGGCAACUUGACUGUCAGUGUUAAAAUGGAAAACAGGAAAAUGGAAAAAUCUGACCAAUUCUGCCACCUUGAGACUUUCAUAUAGACCUUGCACAACAAUUGUAUAGAUCACACACCGGCUGUAUUUAAUAUGUAACAUUUUCACACAUAUUAAAGAUACAGAAGUAUUAAAAAACCCCCAAUGUUAAUGUAUUUGCUUAAAAGGCACAAGUUUCACAUAUCUGUCUAGCUAUCUGUUGGUAAUACAGAAAGUAUACUACUUUUUUAAAAAAGUGGGCAGAAUUCUUGUGUAUGUAUAUUUGUGUGUACAGUAUGUGUAUGUGUGUAUAUAUAUAUAUUAUAUAUAUAGAUAAUAUAUAAAUAUUUUUUUUAAGGAGAAACUAGAAUGUUUAGCUAGAAAAUUCCACAGCCUGUGAAGAAAUAUUUCAAAAUGGCCAUAAAGGAGGUAAAAAUGAAAACCAUAACCUAACUUUUAUAGAGGCUUUAUCUUUAAUUUAACGAUGUGCGGAGGACUUUCUUGCUUGAAUCUGUUCCGGGCUGUCUGCUCUGUCCAUCAAAUGGGCAGGUCUGGAAUGGGGCACCUUCGGCCGUUCAGAAGUGGCCUGAACAGAAUGCUGGAACCCAGGCUGGACUCGGACACACUAAGGUUUUGAUUUUGAAUUUCAGCCUUAUUAGAAGAUCUAACCUAAGAGUAAGCUAACCACAGGGAUUCUUUUGUAGAACACUUUUUAUGCAGAUGAAGCUAUUUUUUCCAGCAAGUAGAUUCUUCCAGUUUUUCCAAGGAGUAAUUUCCCCGAAUUGGCAUACCACGGCGUGGACAGCUGAUAUUUCACCCAGCUGCUGGCUUGUGGGUGUGGCUCUUUGCUUUAUAUAUAUAUACACACAUGUGAGUCUGGCUGGGCUGGUAUUUUGUUUGAUCUUCCUGGAAAUGAGCAGUGACUAACGCUCACAUAACUGGUUUUUUUUUUAUCUGGGCUGAUGAAUACAUUUACCUAAGAAACUCAUUUCGUUUUACUUAAGAGGGGAAGUGCAGUUUUCUUUUGGCAGUUCAGAAUCCAAGCACUUGAUUUGCUGGGUUUGGAAAACUCCUUUUUUGGCCUUCUAUGUGCUUAGCCAUAACAAUUCCAUUAAGCAAGAAGGUAAGCAAAAGACAAAAAAAAAAAAAGGAAAAAAAAAAACUUGCACUGGCUUGUCUCACUUACGAAACAUGUCGGAGCUGUUUGCCUGGGUGGGGCUGGGUACCGUACCUGUCAAUGCCUGUGAUUUUCAUAAUUAGCACGUACAUAAAGAAGUACAUUCUGUUCAGGUGAUAACUGAGCCUCAAUCAAGCAGAAACUUUUUGCUUGAAAUUAAAAAAAAAUUUCUAUUAGUGAAAUUUCUUUUUUUUUUUUUUUUGGAAGCACCCUGUUAUCUAAAGAAUCUUUGUAAGAUUUUUGUAAAAUUUUGUUUUACAAGAUUUUAUUUGAAAUUGUUUUUUGCAAGAUUGUUAUAUUUCUGUAUGAAUGUAUUUUUUAUUGGAAUAACAUAAAAGAAUUCUUAUCAGCAUCUUGAGUCUGGUUGUUUUUUUUGGGGGAAGGGGGUUGUUGGAACAGAUUCCUCCUGCAUUCAUCACCCUGGCUUCCUCCUGGGGGCAAAUCUUCAUUGAGCAACCCUGAGAACAACUCACCGACCUCAGCCCCUUCCUCUUUCCACAGCCUGUCCUGGGAGCUGGAGAGGAUGUCAGCGAGCCUGACAUUGCCCUCCCUGAAUGCAUCAAAUACUCUUCUCCAAGGACUGACAAAAACAACCCCCCGGCUGUGGGCACAGUAGGGAACCAUGCCGGUUUGAUCUUCCAUUGCUCAAGCCAGGGAAUGCAUUGCAGAGGCACCUGCACAACGACAAACUUGAGUGUUUCCCUGCCACUUCUGUGCCUCCACAGCCUGCUCCAGUUCCGCAGCUAGAGCUGGGCCUACCUUCCCCAGCCAGCCCUGCCACACACCUGGCUGAGGCAUGUCUGGGAGGGGUGGAGGAGGCAGAGGGACUCCAGGCCAGAGGGCUGUUCUCACAACCUCAGCCCACUCUCAGUCAAGGAGGGCAGAAAAUAAAAGAUGACAUCACUGCCA